AGACGCCCCUAGGGGGCCAGCGAGGGCGGGUCCCAGGUGCAGCGGAUGCAGAGGAGAGAGGCCCGGGCGCGGCGCGGGGGAUGGUGCGAUCCCGGGCCCGAGGGCAUCAGACGGCGGCUGAUUAGCUCCGGUUUGCAUCACCCGGACCGGGGGAUUAGCUCCGGUUUGCAUCACCCGGACCGGGGGAUUAGCUCCGGUUUGCAUCACCCGGACCGGGGGCCGGGCGCGCACGAGACUCGCAGCGGAAGUGGAGGCGGCUCCGCGCGCGUCCGCUGCUAGGACCCGGGCAGGGCUGGAGCUGGGCUGGGAUCCCGAGCUCGGCAGCAGCGCAGCGGGCCGGCCCACCUGCUGGUGCCCUGGAGGCUCUGAGCCCCGGCGGCGCCCGGGCCCACGCGGAACGACGGGGCGAGAUGCGAGCCACCCCUCUGGCUGCUCCUGCGGGUUCCCUGUCCAGGAAGAAGCGGUUGGAGUUGGAUGACAACUUAGAUACCGAGCGUCCCGUCCAGAAACGAGCUCGAAGUGGGCCCCAGCCCAGACUGCCCCCCUGCCUGUUGCCCCUGAGCCCACCUACUGCUCCAGAUCGUGCAACUGCUGUGGCCACUGCCUCCCGUCUUGGGCCCUAUGUCCUCCUGGAGCCCGAGGAGGGCGGGCGGGCCUACCAGGCCCUGCACUGCCCUACAGGCACUGAGUAUACCUGCAAGGUGUACCCCGUCCAGGAAGCCCUGGCCGUGCUGGAGCCCUAUGCGCGGCUGCCCCCGCACAAGCAUGUGGCUCGGCCCACUGAGGUCCUGGCUGGUACCCAGCUCCUCUACGCCUUUUUCACUCGGACCCAUGGGGACAUGCACAGCCUGGUGCGAAGCCGCCACCGUAUCCCUGAGCCUGAGGCUGCCGUGCUCUUCCGCCAGAUGGCCACCGCCCUGGCGCACUGUCACCAGCACGGUCUGGUCCUGCGUGAUCUCAAGCUGUGUCGCUUUGUCUUCGCUGACCGUGAGAGGAAGAAGCUGGUGCUGGAGAACCUGGAGGACUCCUGCGUGCUGACUGGGCCAGAUGAUUCCCUGUGGGACAAGCACGCGUGCCCAGCCUACGUGGGACCUGAGAUACUCAGCUCACGGGCCUCAUACUCGGGCAAGGCAGCCGAUGUCUGGAGCCUGGGCGUGGCGCUCUUCACCAUGCUGGCCGGCCACUACCCCUUCCAGGACUCGGAGCCUGUCCUGCUCUUCGGCAAGAUCCGCCGCGGGGCCUACGCCUUGCCUGCAGGCCUCUCGGCCCCUGCCCGCUGUCUGGUUCGCUGCCUCCUUCGUCGGGAGCCAGCUGAACGGCUCACAGCCACAGGCAUCCUCCUGCACCCCUGGCUGCGACAGGACCCGAUGCCCUUAGCCCCAACCCGAUCCCAUCUCUGGGAGGCUGCCCAGGUGGUCCCUGAUGGACUGGGGCUGGACGAAGCCAGGGAAGAGGAGGGAGACAGAGAAGUGGUUCUGUAUGGCUAGGACCACCCUACUACACGCUCAGCUGCCAACAGUGGAUUGAGUUUGGGGGUAGCUCCAAGCCUUCUCCUGCCUCUGAACUGAGCCAAACCUUCAGUGCCUUCCAGAAGGGAGAAAGGCAGAAGCCUGUGUGGAGUGUGCUGUGUACACAUCUGCUUUGUUCCACACACAUGCAGUUCCUGCUUGGGUGCUUAUCAGGUGCCAAGCCCUGUUCUCGGUGCUGGGAGUACAGCAGUGAGCAAAGGAGACAAUAUUCCCUGCUCACAGAGAUGACAAACUGGCAUCCUUGAGCUGACAACACUUUUCCAUGACCAUAGGUCACUGUCUACACUGGGUACACUUUGUACCAGUGUCGGCCUCCACUGAUGCUGGUGCUCAGGCACCUCUGUCCAAGGACAAUCCCUUUCACAAACAAACCAGCUGCCUUUGUAUCUUGUACCUUUUCAGAGAAAGGGAGGUAUCCCUGUGCCAAAGGCUCCAGGCCUCUCCCCUGCAACUCAGGACCCAAGCCCAGCUCACUCUGGGAACUGUGUUCCCAGCAUCUCUGUCCUCUUGAUUAAGAGAUUCUCCUUCCAGGCCUAAGCCUGGGAUUUGGGCCAGAGAUAAGAAUCCAAACUAUGAGGCUAGUUCUUGUCUAACUCAAGACUGUUCUGGAAUGAGGGUCCAGGCCUGUCAACCAUGGGGCUUCUGACCUGAGCACCAAGGUUGAGGGACAGGAUUAGGCAGGGUCUGUCCUGUGGCCACCUGGAAAGUCCCAGGUGGGACUCUUCUGGGGACACUUGGGGUCCACAAUCCCAGGUCCAUACUCUAGGUUUUGGAUACCAUGAGUAUGUAUGUUUACCUGUGCCUAAUAAAGGAGAAUUAUGAAAUAA